AGUUCCCGUUCCGGGCCCGCGAGGCAGCCGCCCCGGUCCUGCCCCUCCCUCGCGCUACUGCGGGAGCAGCGUCCUCCCGGGCCACGGCGCUUCCCGGCCCCGGCGUCCCCGGACCAUGGCGCUCUCCGGGCUCUUCUCUAGCUCUCAGCGGCUGCGAAGUCUGUAAACCUGGUGGCCAAGGACAGUCAGUUGCAUGUCACACAAGGGGCCUCCUUUGAUUUAUCCAAAAGGUCUGACCUGGUUUCUGGAAAAACUCUUUAGCGCAUCAAAUACUCGUUGAGGGCAAGUGUUGUUUCUAAACUUGACUCUUGUGGUGAGAGCAUCUCAGUUAUAAGAAAUGCACAUCUCCGCUCAAGGUCCCCUGGGACAGUGCAAGGAAAGAAAGAAGCCUGCGGUGAAAGUGACACUGAGUGAGUGUGUAUCUGUGGUUUCUCUGGGGCCACCCCAGGAUUCAGGGACAGAGUCCUGGUUGCUCUCCAGGAGGUGAUUGUAAGUCAGGAGACUUUCCUUCGGUUUCUGCCUUUGAUGGCAAGAGGUGGAGAUUGUGGCGGCGAUUACAGAAAACAUCUGGGAAGACAAGUUGCUGUUUUUAUGGGAAUCGCAGGCUUGGAAGAGACAGAAGCAAUUCCAGAAAUAAAUUGGAAAUUGAAGAUUUAAACAAUGUUGUUUUAAAAUAUUCUAACUUCAAAGAAUGAUGCCAGAAACUUAAAAAGGGGCUGCGCAGAGUAGCAGGGGCCCUGGAGGGCGCGGCCUGAAUCCUGAUUGCCCUUCUGCUGAGAGGACACACGCAGCUGAAGAUGAAUUUGGGAAAAGUAGCCGCUUGCUACUUUAACUAUGGAAGAGCAGGGCCACAGUGAGAUGGAAAUAAUCCCAUCAGAGUCUCACCCCCACAUUCAAUUACUGAAAAGCAAUCGGGAACUUCUGGUCACUCACAUCCGCAAUACUCAGUGUCUGGUGGACAACUUGCUGAAGAAUGACUACUUCUCGGCCGAAGAUGCGGAGAUUGUGUGUGCCUGCCCCACCCAGCCUGACAAGGUGCCCCGGGGACAGGGACGGGCAUGGCAUUGUGUGGACCCCGGGAGCUAGAAGAGGCCUCUCCCUGCUGAUCUGAGUGAAGAGCGUGGGAGUUUAGUCCAGCGGGCAGGGCUGCAUUUUGGGGUACUAAUAGCACACAAAUGCCUGGGUUAGCAGGUUGCACAGUCAGGUAUUUUACUUCUGUGUUUGUGUCUGGAGCAAACCCUGACAUCUCAGUUCUCAUUGCUGUGUGUAUUGGUUCCCAGACACUUCAUUUUUAGAUCCCCUUUAAAUUAGGAGGGAAAAAGAACAUAAGCAUAAGAGCAUCCCCAGCAGCGAUGUUCAUUCAGUGCCUCUGAAGGCUGGAGGGCUGCUUGUUGCUGGGUGAGACUCGGAGGGGAACCGACUCAGGGUCAGGAAUGAUGACAUCCCACGGUGGGUCCACAGUGAAGAAUCUUCCCCGCUCCACUGUGGGACGCCUUAACAGCCCUUACUUCCACUUACGCUUUGCGUUAUCUCCUGAAAAAUAAAAUGGAGACCACAAAUUCCUUCUUGGUUAGAGGAAUGACACAACUCAUUUAUGACAUGACCCCGCUGGGACUCAGAAGAGACCAGGACGGUUUCUGGGGGAAGCAGUAGCACACUCGUGUGCUUUGUUCUCUUCUCUUGAUUUGUUUUCCCACAUUUUUAACAAGAAAAAAAGCCGUUUUUAAUAUAUGGCCUAUCGCCCUCCUACUGUGUGGCCCAGGUGCCUACCUCAUUAUGCCCAAGGGGUGGUUCUCACCUCUCCACUCUCAUUCCUGCACAGCAGUUGUGUCAGGUUAAGAGGGACAAGGAGAAGGCUGGGCACCGUGGCUCACGCCUGUAAUCCCAGCACUUUGGGAGGCCGAGGCAGGCAGAUCACCUAAGGUCAGGAGUUUGAGACCAGCCUGGCCAACAUGGGGAAAACCCGUCUCUAAUAAAAACACAAAAAUUAGUCGGGCAUGGUGGUGGGUGCCUGUAAUCCCAGCCACUUGGGAGGCUGAGGAAAGAGAAUUCCUUGAACCUGGGAGGUGGAGGUUGCAGUGAGCCAAGAUUGUGCCAUUGCACUCCAGCCCUCCAGCCUGGGUGACAGAGCAAGACUCUGUCUCAAAAAAGAAAAAAAAAAAAAAGAGGUAGAGAAGUCCAUGGCUAUUUGUCUGUCCUUUUUAUUUUUAGGCUCAUGGAAGCCUCCUGGUUUCUUAGAGCUGAGUGGUUUUAUUUCUUGCUCAGGAGGUCAUUUCACAGAUUUUCGGGCUCCAAUAUGUUGACUGUCACAGCAGCUGGGGGGAUGGCAUAGCUACCGGCUGUACUAAGAACUCAGAGCCCUGCCCUGAGCCUGCCUGAGGGUCCUUAUGGUAGGAGGAUGCCCCUCAUGCCAGCCCGUGCCCUCAUGCUUGUGUCACCUCCAGGUCCGCAAAAUUCUGGACCUGGUACAGAGCAAGGGCGAGGAGGUGUCCGAGUUCUUCCUCUACUUGCUCCAGCAACUCGCAGAUGCCUACGUGGACCUCAGGCCUUGGCUGCUGGAGAUCGGCUUCUCCCCUUCCCUGCUCACUCAGAGCAAAGUCGUGGUCAACACUGACCCAGUGAGCAGGUAUACCCAGCAGCUGCGACACCAUCUGGGCCGUGACUCCAAGUUCGUGCUGUGCUAUGCCCAGAAGGAGGAGCUGCUGCUGGAGGAGAUCUACAUGGACACCAUCAUGGAGCUGGUUGGCUUCAGCAAUGAGAGCCUGGGCAGCCUGAACAGCCUGGCCUGCCUCCUGGACCACACCACCGGCAUCCUCAAUGAGCAGGGUGAGACCAUCUUCAUCCUGGGUGAUGCUGGGGUGGGCAAGUCCAUGCUGCUACAGCGGCUGCAGAGCCUCUGGGCCACGGGCCGGCUAGACGCAGGGGUCAAAUUCUUCUUCCACUUUCGCUGCCGCAUGUUCAGCUGCUUCAAGGAAAGUGACAGGCUGUGUCUGCAGGACCUGCUCUUCAAGCACUACUGCUACCCAGAGCGGGACCCCGAGGAGGUGUUUGCCUUCCUGCUGCGCUUCCCCCACGUGGCCCUCUUCACCUUCGAUGGCCUGGACGAGCUGCACUCGGACUUGGACCUGAGCCGCGUGCCUGACAGCUCCUGCCCCUGGGAGCCUGCCCACCCCCUGGUCUUGCUGGCCAACCUGCUCAGUGGGAAGCUGCUCAAGGGGGCUAGCAAGCUGCUCACAGCCCGCACAGGCAUCGAGGUCCCGCGCCAGUUCCUGCGGAAGAAGGUGCUUCUCCGGGGCUUCUCCCCCAGCCACCUGCGCGCCUAUGCCAGGAGGAUGUUCCCCGAGCGGGCCCUGCAGGACCGCCUGCUGAGCCAGCUGGAGGCCAACCCCAACCUCUGCAGCCUGUGCUCUGUGCCCCUCUUCUGCUGGAUCAUCUUCCGGUGCUUCCAGCACUUCCGUGCUGCCUUUGAAGGCUCACCACAGCUGCCCGACUGCACGAUGACCCUGACAGAUGUCUUCCUCCUGGUCACUGAGGUCCAUCUGAACAGGAUGCAGCCCAGCAGCCUGGUGCAGCGGAACACACGCAGCCCAGUGGAGACCCUCCACGCCGGCCGGGACACUCUGUGCUCGCUGGGGCAGGUGGCCCACCGGGGCAUGGAGAAGAGCCUCUUUGUCUUCACCCAGGAGGAGGUGCAGGCCUCCGGGCUGCAGGAGAGAGACAUGCAGCUGGGCUUCCUGCGGGCUUUGCCGGAGCUGGGCCCCGGGGGUGACCAGCAGUCCUAUGAGUUUUUCCACCUCACCCUCCAGGCCUUCUUUACAGCCUUCUUCCUCGUGCUGGACGACAGGGUGGGCACUCAGGAGCUGCUCAGGUUCUUCCAGGAGUGGAUGCCCCCUGCGGGGGCAGCGACCACGUCCUGCUAUCCUCCCUUCCUCCCGUUCCAGUGCCUGCAGGGCAGUGGUCCGGCGCGGGAAGACCUCUUCAAGAACAAGGAUCACUUCCAGUUCACCAACCUCUUCCUGUGCGGGCUGUUGUCCAAAGCCAAACAGAAACUCCUGCGGCAUCUGGUGCCCGCGGCAGCCCUGAGGAGAAAGCGCAAGGCCCUGUGGGCACACCUGUUUUCCAGCCUGCGGGGCUACCUGAAGAGCCUGCCCCGCGUUCAGGUCGAAAGCUUCAACCAGGUGCAGGCCAUGCCCACGUUCAUCUGGAUGCUGCGCUGCAUCUACGAGACACAGAGCCAGAAGGUGGGGCAGCUGGCGGCCAGGGGCAUCUGCGCCAACUACCUCAAGCUGACCUACUGCAACGCCUGCUCGGCCGACUGCAGCGCCCUCUCCUUCGUCCUGCAUCACUUCCCCAAGCGGCUGGCCCUAGACCUAGACAACAACAAUCUCAACGACUACGGCGUGCGGGAGCUGCAGCCCUGCUUCAGCCGCCUCACUGUUCUCAGACUCAGCGUAAACCAGAUCACUGACGGUGGGGUAAAGGUGCUAAGCGAAGAGCUGACCAAAUACAAAAUUGUGACCUAUUUGGGUUUAUACAACAACCAGAUCACCGAUGUCGGAGCCAGGUACGUCACCAAAAUCCUGGAUGAAUGCAAAGGCCUCACGCAUCUUAAACUGGGAAAAAACAAAAUAACAAGUGAAGGAGGGAAGUAUCUCGCCCUGGCUGUGAAGAACAGCAAAUCAAUCUCUGAGGUUGGGAUGUGGGGCAAUCAAGUUGGGGAUGAAGGAGCAAAAGCCUUCGCAGAGGCUCUGCGGAACCACCCCAGCUUGACCACCCUGAGUCUUGCGUCCAACGGCAUCUCCACAGAAGGAGGAAAGAGCCUUGCGAGGGCCCUGCAGCAGAACACGUCUCUAGAAAUACUGUGGCUGACCCAAAAUGAACUCAACGAUGAAGUGGCAGAGAGUUUGGCAGAAAUGUUGAAAGUCAACCAGACGUUAAAGCAUUUAUGGCUUAUCCAGAAUCAGAUCACAGCUAAGGGGACUGCCCAGCUGGCAGAUGCGUUACAGAGCAACACUGGCAUAACAGAGAUUUGCCUAAAUGGAAACCUGAUAAAACCAGAGGAGGCCAAAGUCUAUGAAGAUGAGAAGCGGAUUAUCUGUUUCUGAGAGGAUGCUUUCCUGUUCAUGGGGUUUUUGCCCUGGAGCCUCAGCAGCAAAUGCCACUCUGGGCAGUCUUUUGUGUCAGUGUCUUAAAGGGGCCUGCGCAGGCGGGACUAUCAGGAGUCCACUGCCUCCAUGAUGCAAGCCAGCUUCCUGUGCAGAAGGUCUGGUCGGCAAACUCCCUAAGUACCCGCUACAAUUCUGCAGAAAAAGAAUGUGUCUUGCGAGCUGUUGUAGUUACAGUAAAUACACUGUGAAGAGACUUUAUUGCCUAUUAUAAUUAUUUUUAUCUGAAGCUAGAGGAAUAAAGCUGUGAGCAAACAGAGGAGGCCAGCCUCACCUCAUUCCAACACCUGCCAUAGGGACCAACGGGAGCGAGUUGGUCACCGCUCUUUUCAUUGAAGAGUUGAGGAUGUGGCACAAAGUUGGUGCCAAGCUUCUUGAAUAAAACGUGUUUGAUGGAUUAGUAUUAUACCUGAAAUAUUUUCUUCCUUCUCAGCACUUUCCCAUGUAUUGAUACUGGUCCCACUUCACAGCUGGAGACACCGGAGUAUGUGCAGUGUGGGAUUUGACUCCUCCAAGGUUUUGUGGAAAGUUAAUGUCAAGGAAAGGAUGCACCACGGGCUUUUAAUUUUAAUCCUGGAGUCUCACUGUCUGCUGGCAAAGAUAGAGAAUGCCCUCAGCUCUUAGCUGGUCUAAGAAUGACGAUGCCUUCAAAAUGCUGCUUCCACUCAGGGCUUCUCCUCUGCUAGGCUACCCUCCUCUAGAAGGCUGAGUACCAUGGGCUACAGUGUCUGGCCUUGGGAAGAAGUGAUUCUGUCCCUCCAAAGAAAUAGGGCAUGGCUUGCCCCUGUGGCCCUGGCAUCCAAAUGGCUGCUUUUGUCUCCCUUACCUCGUGAAGAGGGGAAGUCUCUUCCUGCCUCCCAAGCAGCUGAAGGGUGACUAAACGGGCGCCAAGACUCAGGGGAUCGGCUGGGAACUGGGCCAGCAGAGCAUGUUGGACACCCCCCACCAUGGUGGGCUUGUGGUGGCUGCUCCAUGAGGGUGGGGGUGAUACUACUAGAUCACUUGUCCUCUUGCCAGCUCAUUUGUUAAUAAAAUACUGAAAACACUCUUA